GGGCACUUCCGCGGCAAGAGGUUGAGAGCGCGGCCUUCAUUCCUCUCGUGGAAGUGAGUGAGUCCUGGGACCCCGCGACCUGUUUUAACUUUUAUGGUUUGGUCGUAGGAUCAGCAGGGCUCGCACUUCGGUCAGCAGGAAAAGACGCUGCGGCGAGCAGCGGAGGGCGGAGUUGAAUGGCUGGGCAGCUGAUUGCCUUACUGUAUCCGGAGCUGCUGCGUUCGGGGCGGUUCGGGAGUCCCCUGGUUGGAAGUGGACCUGAAUGGGGAGGCGUCUGAGGAUCUCCUGGGCUCUCAGCGGCCCGACCCGCCUUCCCCCACCUCCCACAGCUCUGUAGCUUCCUAGCGGUGUAACGUUGGGAAAGGAGGCUGUUCUUGGACUAUGCCUGACCCGUUUUUUAAGAAAGAGUGCAUCACUCAACAGGUGGCGUCUGGAGUUAUCCUCUGUGGAUUUUCCAGGAUCUCAGACAAGAUCGUGCAAUCUCCCAGCCUCCUUUCCUUCCCCUGCCCUGACUUCUGAAAGAAUGCUGCGGGAGAGGAGGAAGGAGAGCAUCCUGGCUUCUGGCAGCAGAGCCCCACUGUGACAGGACCUAGCAUUCACCUUCCUCUUCUGUUCCGAGUGCGAGAAGACUUCAGGGACCUCUGUUUCAUGGACAUUAUCAUAUUCUUCUCAAGAGUACCCAGCAAGAGGUUUGCAAAGAGGAGUUAUUCAGUGAAGACGGGGUUUCACCAUCUUGGCUAGGCUGGUCUUGAAUUCCUGACCUCGUGAUCCACCCGCCUGGGCCUCCCAAAGUGCUGGGAUUACAUGCGUGAGCCACCGUGCCCAGCCUCAAAGCAGCAAAAAUGGACUAAGACAUCACUUGAACUGGCAGGAGGUGGCUGAACACACAAACCCUACAGUCAGCCUAUGCAGAAGAGAAUCAGAAUCAUACCCUGAGAGCUACAAGAACUCCAUUUUUCACUGUGCAGAGGCUCUCUGCUGAAGGGUCAAGUGGAAUCUGGAAUCCAGCCCAUGUUUCCCCAUCAUCAAGCCAUGUGAAGCUGCAGACUCCAAGCAACAGAGAGACAAGAUUUAGAAUACUGGCUCUGGUAUGAAAGCUGGAUUCAGGUACUGUUCCUGCCUCUUGACCUCACCAAGCCUCAGCUUCCUCGCCUGUUAAAUGGAUACAAUUGUCGUCAUUAUCAUCUGUUGAGAACUCCCUAAAAUGCCAGCUGAGCAUAGGCACAGAAGUUUAGGUGUUUGGACCAAGGUCACACAACUGAUACAACAGUAGCUUCUUCACAGACUUGGCACUUCUCCAGAAGGAGGAGGACAAAAUGACGAAGUCUAAGUGCUAUCCCUUUUCCAGUGGACCUUUAUUGCAAGAUUUAGGUGGAGUGUGUUUGAUGUUGUAGGAGGCAGUGACAUUCAAGGACGUGGCUGUGGUCUUCUCUGAGGAGGAGCUGCAACUGCUGGACCUUGCCCAGAGGAAGCUGUACCGAGAUGUGAUGCUGGAGAACUUCAGGAAUGUGGUCUCAGUGGGGCAUCAGUCCACACCAGAUGGCCUACCACAGUUAGAGAGAGAAGAAAAGCUGUGGAUGAUGAAGAUGGCAACCCAGAGAGAUAACUCCUCAGGAGCCAAGAAUCUAAAAGAGAUGGAGACUCUUCAAGAAGUAGGAUUAAGGUACCUGCCUCAUGAAGAGCUUUUCUGCUCCCAGAUCUGGCAACAGAUUACAAGAGAGUUAAUCAAGUAUCAAGAUUCUGUGGUAAAUAUUCAAAGAACAGGCUGCCAGUUGGAAAAACGAGAUGAUUUGCACUAUAAAGAUGAGGGAUUCAGUAAUCAGAGUUCCCAUCUUCAAGUUCACAGAGUCCACACUGGUGAAAAACCCUACAAAGGAGAACAUUGUGUGAAAAGUUUCAGCUGGAGCUCUCAUCUUCAAAUUAACCAAAGGGCUCAUGCAGGAGAGAAGCCCUACAAAUGUGAAAAAUGUGAUAAUGCCUUCCGUCGGUUUUCAAGUCUUCAAGCCCAUCAGAGAGUCCACAGUAGAGCAAAAUCAUACACAAAUGAUGCAAGUUACAGGAGUUUUAGUCAGAGGUCACAUCUUCCCCAUCAUCAGAGAGUUCCCACUGGAGAGAAUCCAUACAAAUAUGAAGAGUGUGGGAGGAAUGUUGGGAAAAGCUCACAUUGUCAAGCUCCUCUGAUAGUUCAUACGGGAGAGAAACCCUAUAAAUGUGAGGAGUGUGGGGUGGGCUUCAGUCAGAGAUCAUAUCUUCAAGUUCAUCUGAAAGUUCACACUGGAAAGAAACCAUAUAAGUGUGAAGAGUGUGGGAAGAGCUUCAGUUGGCGUUCACGACUGCAGGCUCAUGAGCGAAUCCACACUGGCGAGAAACCAUACAAAUGCAAUGCAUGUGGCAAGAGCUUUAGUUACAGCUCACACCUUAAUAUUCAUUGUAGAAUCCACACAGGAGAGAAACCCUAUAAGUGUGAGGAGUGUGGGAAAGGUUUCAGUGUGGGUUCACACCUUCAGGCCCAUCAGAUAAGCCACACUGGAGAGAAGCCAUACAAAUGUGAGGAGUGUGGGAAAGGCUUCUGCCGGGCCUCAAAUCUGCUGGACCAUCAAAGAGGCCAUACUGGAGAGAAACCGUAUCAGUGUGAUGCAUGUGGUAAGGGCUUCAGUCGUAGCUCAGAUUUUAACAUUCAUUUUAGAGUCCAUACAGGGGAAAAACCCUAUAAAUGUGAGGAGUGUGGCAAGGGCUUCAGCCAGGCCUCAAAUCUUCUGGCCCAUCAAAGAGGCCACACUGGAGAGAAACCCUACAAAUGUGGUACAUGUGGGAAGGGCUUCAGUCGGAGCUCAGAUCUUAAUGUACACUGUAGAAUCCACACAGGAGAGAAACCCUAUAAAUGCGAGAGGUGUGGUAAGGCCUUCAGUCAGUUCUCCAGCCUUCAGGUGCAUCAGAGAGUUCACACUGGAGAGAAACCAUAUCAGUGUGCAGAGUGUGGGAAGGGCUUCAGUGUAGGUUCACAGCUUCAAGCCCAUCAGAGGUGCCACACUGGAGAGAAACCCUAUCAAUGUGAGGAGUGUGGGAAGGGCUUCUGUCGGGCCUCCAAUUUUCUGGCACAUCGUGGAGUCCACACAGGAGAAAAACCAUACCGAUGUGAUGUGUGUGGUAAGCGCUUCAGACAGAGAUCCUACCUUCAAGCCCACCAGAGGGUCCACACAGGAGAGAGACCAUACAAAUGUGAGGAAUGUGGGAAAGUCUUCAGCUGGAGCUCAUACCUUCAAGCCCAUCAAAGAGUUCACACCGGAGAAAAACCAUACAAAUGUGAGGAGUGUGGGAAGGGCUUCAGUUGGAGCUCAAGUCUUAUCAUUCAUCAGCGAGUCCAUGCUGAUGAUGAGGGUGACAAGGACUUUCCUUCAUCAGAGGAUUCACACAGGAAAACUCGAUAAAAUAUGUUUUACUAUCUCAGAUGGGUGCUGAAAUAUUUUAAUAAUCAGAGCUAUCAUAGACAAAACAUUUGUUUUAUAGAGUCAGUAGUUCAGCCAAGUGAUUGGGAGACCACACAGCAGAGAAGCCUCACAAGAGUGGAGACAUAUGGACUGCAUUCAGAACAUUGACCAUUAGCUGAUACAUGCAGACAAGAGGAUCAGGAAGGAUGAGUCUGAUCUGGAGUAAAUCAGAAGUACUAAGAUAGAAAUGCUGAAUUCUGUUCCACUAGAAUAUAAGAUCCAAGAGGGCAGGGACUUUGUUGACUGCCAAAUCUACUCUGCCUUUUCAGUGCCUAAUACGUUGUAAUUUUUCAGUAGUAUUUGAAAUUACUGUCAUAUUUGAAAUUCAGUAAUAUUUGACAUUUUUAUUUAUCUCUAGAAGUUUCUCUAAAAUUGUACUCAGAAGAAUUCUGCAAGGCUUGGAGGAUAUAUAAGUUAGUCAUAUGGCCUGAUUUUCCCAUUUUUGCAGAUCUCGUGGACAAGUGUUUAUCAAACUGAAGGUUGCAGCUUGUUAGUGGGUUCAGAAAUCAGUUUCUGGCUAGCAACUAGAAGUUUUGUAUGUUAACAGUACUUUAUUGAGGUGUAAUCUGCAUGCAGUAACAUGCACAAGUCUCAAGUUCAUGGCUUUCUGAAUUUUGACAAAUGUAAUCAUCACCAAGAUCAAUGUAUACAAUAUGUCUAUUAAACCAAAAAGUUUUCUUGUGCCCAUUUCCAGUCAAUCCCA